AUGGCGAUUCUGAGUGUGAGGGCAGACUUCUGCCAGGCUCAGCACAGCAUUUUCGCUGACAAGUGA